AUUUAUUGAGCUUCAGCUGUGUGUCUGGCACUGCGCUGCAAGCUGGGAAUACAAAAAUGAGUAAGAUACACAUCCCUGUCCUCAAAGAGUUUACUUUUUUUUUAAGCCAAGGAGAUAGCAACGGUAUGGCAUGAAGCUAUUGCGGAGGUUUGGUAGAGGAGGACUUAGGGUACGCAUAAGUCAGGCUGACUCAUCAGAGAAGGUUUCAGUGAGGAGGUGCUGCUUUAGCCAAGACCUGAAGGACGAACGAGAUCUGACAGGUGAAGAGUGGUUCGAAGUGAGAUGAGCAAAGGGCUAGAGGUGAGAAUGCAUGGCCUGCUUGUGGUUCACUGGAGUGCCAGUGUGGAGGUGUAGGAUGAGAGGUGACUGGAAAGGUAAGCACUAGCCACAUCGUGAAGGGCCCUGUGGACAAUAGCAUGUUACCCGCACAUAGACUUUGGGAUCCAAGAUAGCUGCGUACCAAUAUUCCCAUUGCCACUGAACUAGUUUUGUGACCCUGGGCAAGUCACUUCUUUCUAAGCUUCAGUUUCCUCAUCUCUAAGAAGGGGAAAUAAAAACUGUACGAGGUGAUAUGUUACUCACUUGACACUGGUAGAUGAUAAAUACUCAAUAAACAGUAGUCAUUAAUAUUGCCAGGCCCAGAAGUUUGGACUCUAAAAUGUGGGGGCGGGGGUGGAGAGCAGGACACUGAAGAUUUUAAAACAGAUGCGACAUCCUCUCAUCUGUUUUAAAUUACCCAGGCAGCAAUGUGGUGAUUACACUGGACAGAAAAAGACAAGCAGGGGACCAGUUGGGUAUAGUUGCAGUGAUCCAGGUGACAGGAUGAAGAUCUGGAUGAAGGCAGUGACAGUGGAGAUGGAGAGGAGUGGGAGGAGUUGAGAGAUUAAGGAGGUGGAAUUUGCUGGACUUGGUAACUGAUAGGAUGAAACAGAAGAAGGGGACAAGAAUCAGGAUCCUGAUGACGGGAGGGCAGAAAUGAAUUUGCUGUGUGGAAUUGAGCAGUAACAAAAUUCUUUGACUAGUGUCUCUAAUAGAUUAACCCUGACCUCUGAUUUUAUUUGGAAUUCAGUUUGCCUCUGUCGUCCACUUCUACCCAUGGAAAUGACGUUCGCUAAUGUCUUCCUCUCCUCUUUUUUUUUUUUUCUUUUUUUUUGAGAUGGAGUCUCACUCUGUCGCCCAGGCUGGAGUGCAGUGGCACGAUCUCGGCUCACUGCAAGCUCUGCCUCCUGGGUUCACUCCAUACUCCUGCCUCAGCCUCCCCAGGAACUGGGACUACAGGUGCCCACCACCAUGCCCGGCUAAUUUUUUUUUUUUUUUUUUUUUUUUAGUAGAGAUGGGGUUUCACUGUGCUAGCCAGGAUGGUCUCCAUCUCCUGACCUCGUGAUCCGCCUGCCUCAGCCUCUCAAAGUGCUGAGAUUACAGGCGUGAGCCACCGCUUCCUCUCCCCUUUCUAUCUCCUGAUCUCCCCACCCUUCUCCAGUGCGAUUAAGGCCUGAUUGUAUAAUCAAGGGACAAUAAAUACUGGAGGUGCUGCUCUGUUAAUUGGUAGUCAGUAGGUAUUACCAUGAUCUUGGCAGACUGAGGAAUAGCCUAUUCACUCCAUCUCAGACCGGCUUCAGAAUGAUCACUUUUGGGAUUUCCUCACACCUUCAUCCCAGUUACCAUCCUUGAACUUGCUCUGGUUUGUCAGCCUCUCUUUGAGUGUGUGGUACAGAAAGGAAAUCCUCUUUCCUUGAGGACUCUAACCAUGCAGAGCAAGACUGCACUUUUCUUGUGGUAACCUAAAGCCCUGCCAGCUCCAUUAUAGACACAUUGUGCUUUUGACACUAUUACACUAGUGUGCCACCAAAUAGGCCCUCAGCGUGGCUCAGCCCUCCCCAUAUCCUCAGGCAGCUCUCUUGUCCAUUUCCCUUUAUGUCUUCCUCAUAUUCAUUCCUCUCCUCAACCUCCUACCUUGACUUUUGCUCCACUAAGUUGCAGCCAUUAAUUAAGGCAUCGCAGCUUCCUCUUCUAUCCUUUACCAACUGAUCUUUAGCUGACCCUAUCCUUUUGCCUUUUAUUCUAAUUCUGUGAAAGAAAUGGUGUUUUAAGACUAAGUCCUCUAUUUGUGCUUGAGAUCCCAUCGCCUCCUUUGCCUCAAGGACUGGGUUCCAUCAUUUGUUCAUUUUCUUUUCUGUUUCAUCAACCCUUCUCAUUUAAAUAUUCUCUGUUUACUCUCAUUUUGGAAAAAACAAAAACCCUCCAAUUAACCUAUGCUGCACCCUGUCACACCUCUUUUACCCAGCCACCUUUCUUGGAAGAGUUAUCUAGAGUUGCUUCCUGUACUUCCCUAAGUCAUUGCUAAAAUCCUGCUCUCGUCCCACCACUCCCCAAAGUCAUCAGACCUCGACAUUGCCAGAAUACCUGACCACUUUUCCUUCUUAUCUUUCUUGGCACAUCUGACAUUGCUGACCUUGCCCCUCACUUAGGAAAACCCAGUCCUACUUUGUAUUAUCUCUCUGGCCAUUUGUCCCUCAAUUUCCAUUGUGGGCUCCUUUCUUCCCCUUUGUCCCUCACAUGCCAAUUUUUGCCAAGACUCUGCCCUCUACUAUAUUCUUUUCAACCGCAGCUUCAAACUUGUUUAUAUGCUCAUGACCCCUGUUCUGUAUCAUAGCCCGAAUCUCUCCUGAGUGCUACCCUCAAACUCAAACAAGUCUAAAACUAAGCUCCUCAUCUUCCCUUUGAACCUGCCGUUCUUUCUCCAUUCUUGAAUCUUGCCAAUUCCUCUCCUUUCAUUUAGUCAUCCAAAACAGAACCCUGAGAGUCAUCUCAGACUCUUCCUCUGGUACUAGCCCUCCUUUCCAUCUUCCAAGUCCAGGUAGUCAUCAGAGUUCUAUAGAUUCGACUUUGUUGCUAUCUCCUGACUCACAUCUCCUCCAUUUCCUCCCUUGCUCCCUCAUUUCAGGCUCCCCUCCCUUUUUGCCUGUCUUUCUGCACAGCCUCCCAGCUGGUUGCCCUGCCUCAGCAGUCUGGUCCUCACUGCUGUGGAUUGCCUUUACUAAAAUAGAGAUCUAUGCAGAAAUACAGUUGCAUAGCUUUUCACAUAAGGCUCUUCAUGAUAUGGCCUUUGCCUGCUUUUAUGGCAUGGUCCAUCUACUCUGCCCCAUGUGCCUCUCCUUGCUGCCAUACAGAACUCUAUCAGGGGAACCUGCCCCCAAUAUUUCAAGGUAUGUUCUUUCUAUUUUCCAUAAGUGUCAGCUGGCUGAGAAAUAAAGAGAAAGAGUACAAAGAGAGGAAUUUUACAGCUGGGCCUCUGGGGGUGACAUCACAUAUUGGUAGGACUGUGAUGCCGACCCGAGCUGCAAAACCAGCAGGUUUUUAUUAAGGACUUCAAAAGGGGAGGGGGUGUGCGAACAGGGAGUGGGUCACAAAGAUCACAUGCUUCUGAGGAAACAGGACAAGGACAAAAUCAGAAACUCCUGAUAAGGGUCUAUGUUCAGCAGUGUAUGUAUUGUCUUGAUAAACAUCUUAAACAACAGAAAACAGGGUUCGAGAGCAGAGAACUGGUCUGACCUCAAAUUUACCAGGGUGGGGUUUCCCAAUCCUAGUAAGCUUGAGGGUACUGCAGGAGAACAGGGCAUAUUUCAGUCCUUAUCUCAACUGCGUAAGACAGACACUCCCAGAGCGGCCCUUUAUAGACCCCCCCCCCCCCACCAGGAAUGCAUUCCUUUCCCAGGGUCUUAAUUAUUAAUAUUUCUUGCUAGGAAAAGAAUUUAGUGAUAUCUUCCCUACUUGCACGUCUGUUUAUAGGCUCUCUGCAAGAACAAAAAUAUGGCUGUAUUCUGCCUGACCCUGUAGGCAGUCAGACCUUAUGGUUGUCUUCCCUUGUUCCCUGAAAAUCACUGUUAUUCUGUUCUUUUUCAAGGUGCACUGAUUUCAUAUUGUUUAAACACACAUGUUUUACAAUCAAUUUGUACAGUUAACACAAUAGUGGUCCUGAGGUGACUUACAUUCUCAGCUUACAAAGAUAACAGGAUUAAGAGAUUAAAGACAGGCAUAAGAAAUUAUAAAAGUAUUAAUUUUUGGAACUGAUAAAUGUCCAUAUUAAAAUGAAAUCUUCACAAUUUAUGUUCAGAGAUUGAAGUAAAGACAGGCAUAAGAAAUUAUAAAAGUAUUAUUUGGGAACUGAUAUAUGUCCAUAUUAAAAUGAAAUCUUCGCAAUUUAUGUUUCUCUGCUGCAGCUCCAGCCGGUCCCUCCGUUCAGGGUCCGUGACUUCCCGCAACAGAACUCAUUUGUAUUUUCUCAAACAUACCAUCCUGGUUUGUUCUUUCAUUGUUUCAGUCAUCAACAAGUAUUUAUUGGGCACCUGUGAGGUGCGAAGACUGGUGUUAGAAAAACAAUGACGAAUAGGGGAAAAUGAGAAGCUGGCACGGUUCCUUUCUCAUAGAAUUUUUAUUUAUUCAUUCUUUGUUUCAGUCAUCAACAAGUAUUUAUUGGGCACCUAUGAGGUGCUAAGUCAGGUGCUAGAAAAACAAUGAUGAAUGGGGGAAAAUGAGAAGCUGACAUGGUUCCUUUCUCAUAGAAUUUUUAUUCUACUGAGGAGGAUAACUGCAUACGUGCUAUGAAGGAUCCAAUUCCUGUAUCUUCACCUUGUCUACCGGGAUUUCUAGAGCAGCCUUGUGAGAGACAUUUCUGAGACCUGUAUGUCCUGCGUCUAUGAUUCUUCCCUGAUCAAGCUGUCACUGUCCCUCCCAUGUAGGCUUCUCAAACCCCAUAAUGCUGGUAUCCAGUGCAUCCGUUCUCAAAAACUGAAGCUGAUGGACACCAGAUUGCAUGUGAAGGUGAAGGAUAUUAUAGCAGAAGGAAACCAAAAUAAAAGAAAAACAGCUCCUGGAAGUAACCAAUGAGAAGGACAGAUAAGAGUUUGAAGACUGUGGAUGUGACUGCUUGUUCCCUGGUUGACACACUGAAGAAGAAAUCAUGUUGAUUCAGAGUUGGCUUGGAGGCAAGAAAUAAUGGCGGCAGCUACGGGGGAUCCUGGACUCUCUAAACUGCAGUUUGCCCCUUUUAGUAGUGCCUUGGAUGUUGGGUUUUGGCAUGAGUUGACCCAGAAGAAGCUGAACGAGUAUCGGCUGGAUGAAGCUCCCAAGGACAUUAAGGGUUAUUACUACAAUGGUGACUCUGCUGGGCUGCCAGCUCGCUUAACAUUGGAGUUCAGUGCUUUUGACAUGAGUGCUCCCACCCCAGCCCGUUGCUGCCCAGCUAUUGGAACACUGUAUAACACCAACACACUCGAGUCUUUCAAGACUGCAGAUAAGAAGCUCCUUUUGGAACAAGCAGCAAAUGAGAUAUGGGAAUCCAUAAAAUCAGGCACUGCUCUUGAAAACCCUGUACUCCUCAACAAGUUCCUCCUCUUGACAUUUGCAGAUCUAAAGAAGUACCACUUCUACUAUUGGUUUUGCUAUCCUGCCCUCUGUCUUCCAGAGAGUUUACCUCUCAUUCAGGGGCCAGUGGGUUUGGAUCAAAGGUUUUCACUAAAACAGAUUGAAGCACUAGAGUGUGCAUAUGAUAAUCUUUGUCAAACAGAAGGAGUCACAGCUCUUCCUUACUUCUUAAUCAAGUAUGAUGAGAACAUGGUGCUGGUUUCCUUGCUUAAACACUACAGUGAUUUCUUCCAAGGUCAAAGGACGAAGAUAACAAUUGGUGUAUAUGAUCCCUGUAACUUAGCCCAGUACCCUGGAUGGCCUUUGAGGAAUUUUUUGGUCCUAGCAGCCCACAGAUGGAGUAGCAGUUUCCAGUCUGUUGAAGUUGUUUGCUUCCGUGACCGUACCAUGCAGGGGGCGAGAGACGUUGCCCACAGCAUCAUCUUCGAAGUGAAGCUUCCAGAAAUGGCAUUUAGCCCAGAUUGUCCUAAAGCAGUUGGAUGGGAAAAGAACCAGAAAGGAGGCAUGGGACCAAGGAUGGUGAACCUCAGUGAAUGUAUGGACCCUAAAAGGUUAGCUGAGUCAUCAGUGGAUCUAAAUCUCAAACUGAUGUGUUGGAGAUUGGUUCCUACUUUAGACUUGGACAAGGUUGUGUCUGUCAAAUGUCUGCUGCUUGGAGCCGGCACCUUGGGUUGCAAUGUAGCUAGGACGUUGAUGGGUUGGGGCGUGAGACACAUCACAUUUGUGGACAAUGCCAAGAUCUCCUACUCCAAUCCUGUGAGGCAGCCUCUCUAUGAGUUUGAAGAUUGCCUAGGGGGUGGUAAGCCCAAGGCUCUGGCAGCAGCGGACCGGCUCCAGAAAAUAUUCCCCGGUGUGAAUGCCAGAGGAUUCAACAUGAGCAUACCUAUGCCUGGGCAUCCAGUGAACUUCUCCAGUGUCACUCUGGAGCAAGCCCGCAGAGAUGUGGAGCAACUGGAGCAGCUCAUCGAAAGCCAUGAUGUCGUCUUCCUAUUGAUGGACACCAGGGAGAGCCGGUGGCUUCCUGCCGUCAUUGCUGCAAGCAAGAGAAAGCUGGUCAUCAAUGCUGCUUUGGGAUUUGACACAUUUGUUGUCAUGAGACAUGGUCUGAAGAAACCAAAGCAGCAAGGAGCUGGGGACUUGUGUCCAAACCACCCUGUGGCAUCUGCUGACCUCCUGGGCUCAUCGCUUUUUGCCAACAUCCCUGGUUACAAGCUUGGCUGCUACUUCUGCAAUGAUGUGGUGGCCCCAGGAGAUUCAACCAGAGACCGGACCUUGGACCAGCAGUGCACUGUGAGUCGUCCAGGACUGGCCGUGAUUGCAGGAGCCCUGGCCGUGGAAUUGAUGGUAUCUGUUUUGCAGCAUCCAGAAGGGGGCUAUGCCAUUGCCAGCAGCAGUGACGAUCGGAUGAAUGAGCCUCCAACCUCUCUUGGGCUUGUGCCUCACCAGAUCCGGGGAUUUCUUUCACGGUUUGAUAAUGUCCUUCCCGUCAGCCUGGCAUUUGACAAAUGUACAGCUUGUUCUUCCAAAGUUCUUGAUCAAUAUGAACGAGAAGGAUUUAACUUCCUAGCCAAGGUGUUUAAUUCUUCACAUUCCUUCUUAGAAGACUUGACUGGUCUUACAUUGCUGCAUCAAGAAACCCAAGCUGCUGAGGAUCAUCUUUCUUUCAUCCGGCCCAAGAAUGGCACCUUCCCCGCCCAUCAGGCCACCUGCACUCAGGAGUCGGCUGCCUGUCCUGAAAUAGAUCUCUACCAGCUCUCAAGCAGAACAAUUCCUUGCAUUCAUACUUGAAUGUAUAAUUUGUGUUAUUACCUCUUAUUUGUCUUUGUAAGUUUGUCCCUGCCCCAGUUUAAAAAAAAAAAAAAAUCUGAGUUACUGCUACUGAACCAAAGGGCCUCAUUCGAGGUCUUCUUUCUCCCCACCCCCUCCCCCAUCCCAGUGAUACAGAUGCUGCCUUGUCUGGUCAGGCCUUCAGGGAGGAUGUCCUGACCCCCUCAACCCCCCAUCUCCAAAGCUGUCCCCUCGCUCUUUGUGCAACUCGCCGCCCACAUCCAGCACAGUAAAAGCAGGCUGUCAGCUGGGAGAGGCUCGCCUUGGAGGACUGUCCUUUCUUUACAUCCUCUUCCCAGGGCUUCAUGCUGCAAAACAGCACAUUCUCAACAUGAAACAAAAAUGGAUUCUGUUUUCUUUUUCACCUAGUGUUUUUGGCCAUACUGUUCUUGGCAGUCAGACUUCCAGGCUUGGGGUAGAAUCGAUAGCUUAAAAGAUAAAUGUUUACACUGGUCAGCAAUGUGCCAUUUGGAGCCUUGGUGCCCCUGGAUAAUUUGCCAGAGUCUGUGGCUUUGUGUCCGGAAUUGGUGGGUUCUUGGUCUCACUGACUUCAAGAAUGAAGCCGCGGACCCUCGCGGUGAGUGUUACAGCUCUUAAGGUGGCGCGUCUGGAGUCUGUCCCUUCUGAUGUUCAGAUGUGUUCGGAGUUUCUUCCUUCUGGUGGGUUCGUGGUCUCGCUGGCUCGGGAGUGAAGCUGCAGACCUUCGCGGUGAGUGUUACAGCUCAUAAAAGCAGCGUGGACCCAAAGAGUGAGCAGUAGCAAGAUUUAUUGCAAAGAGCAAAAGAACAAAGCUUCCACAGCGUGGAAGGGGACCUGAGCGGGUUGCCAAUGCUGGCUCAGGCAGCCUGCUUUUAUUCUCUUAUCUGGCCCCACCCACAUCCUGCUGAUUGGUAGAGCCGAGUGGCCUGUUUUGUCAGGGCGCUGAUUGGUGCGUUUACAAUCCCUGAGCUAGAUACAAAGGUUCUCCAUGUUCCCAUCAUAUUAGUUAGAUACAGAGUUUCGACACACAGGUUCUCCAAGGCCCCACCAGAGCAGCUAGAUACAGAGUGUCGACUGGUGCAUUCACAAACCUUGAGCUAAACACAGGGUGCUGAUUGGUGUAUUUGUAAUCCCUGAGCUAGAUAUAAAGACUCUCCAUGUCCCCACCAGACUCAGGAGCCCAGCUGGCUUCACCUAGUGGAUCCUGCACUGGGGCUGCAGGUGGAGCUGCCUGCCAGUCCCGUACUGUGCGCUCACACUCCUCAGCCCUUGGGCGGUCGAUGGGACUGGGCGCCGUGAGCAGGGGGUGGUGCUCGUCGGGGAGGCUCCGGCCGCACAGGAGCCCAUGGCGGGGGUGGGAGGCUCAGGCAUGGUGGGCUGCAGGUCCUGAGCCCUGCCCCGAGGGAAGGCAGCUAAGGCCCAGCGAGAAAUCGAGCACAGCACCGGUGGGCUGGUACUGCUGGGGUACUCAGUACACCCUCCGCAGCCACUGGCCCAGGUGCUAAGUCCCCCACUGCCUGGGGCCAGCAGGGCUGGCUGGCUGCUCCGAAUGCGGGGCCCACCAAGCCCACACCCACCCAGAACUCCAGCUGGCCUGCAAGCGCCGCAUGCAGCCCUGGUUCCCGCUCGUGCCUCUCCCUCCACACCUCCCUGCAAGCUGAGGGAGUGGGCUCCAGCCUUGGCCAGCCCAGAAAGGGGCUCCCACAGUGCAGUGGGGGGCUGAAGGGCUCCUCAAAUGCCACCAAAGUGGGAGCCCAGGCAGGGGAGGUGCCAAGAGCAAGCGAGGGCUCUGAGGACUGCCAGCAUGCUGUCACCUCUCAGCUUCACCCACCCAGUGACCUUGAGUCUCCUUAACUUUCCAACUAGCCUACCUCCCAGAGGUCCCCCACACCCCUCUCCCCUCCUUCGGCCAGCCCUGAGGGCCAGGCCCUUUCUCACUUCCUGAACCAAGUACUGGAAGUAGAAGAAACUGUUGUCAGGCUCCGAGUUCCACCUCUGGGUCAAGGGCUCCAGAGCCUGGUGCUGCAGCUUGGCCAAGGGAACCCAAAAACCAGGUCAGCAGUACAUCCACUCUCUGAGCUUUGGUUCUGUCAUUGCACAGGAUUAAUGUUCCAUCUCAGAUUAACUCUGAAAUCAAAUGAGGUAAUGUAUUAGUACUUGUGUGUACAGAAUUGGUGGGUUCUUGGUCUCACUGACUUCAAGAAUGAAGCCAUGGACCGUCGCAGUGAGUGUUAACAGUUCUUAAAGCGGCACGUCUGGAGUUAUUUGUUCCUCCUGGUGGGUUCGUGGUCUCGCUGGCUUCAGGAGUGAAGCUGCAGACCUUCACGGUGAGUGUUACAGCUCAUAAAAGCAGUGUGGACCCAAAGAGUGAGCAGUAGCAAGAUUUAUUGCAAAGAGCUAAAGAACAAAGCUUCCAUAGUGUGGAAGGGGACCUGAGCGGGUUGCCAUUGCUGGCUCGGGCAGCCUGCUUUUAUUCUCUUACCUGGCCCCACCCACAUCCUGCUGAUUGGUCCAUUUUACAGAGAGCUGAUUGGUCCAUUUUACAGAGAGCUGAUUGGUGCGUUUACAAUCCCUGAGCUAGACACAAAAGUUCUCCAAGUCCCCACUAGAUUAGCUAGAUACAGAGUGUGGACACAAAGGUUCUCCAAGUCCCCACCAGAGUAGCUAGAUACAGAGUGUCAAUUGGUGCAUUCCCAAAUCCUGAGCUAGACACAGGGUGCUGAUUGGUGUGUUUACAAACCUUGAGCUAGAUACAGAGUGCCGAUUGGUGUAUUUACAAUCCCCUAGCUAGACAUAAAGGUUCUCCAAGUCCCCACCAGACUCAGGAGCCCAGCUGGCUUCACCCAGUGGAUCCCGCACCGGGGCUGCAGGUGGAGCUGCCUGCCAGUCCUGCGCCGUGCGUCUGCACUCCUCAGCCCUUGGGUGGUGGAUGAGACUGGGCGCCGUGGAGCAGGGGGCGGUGCUCGUUGGGGAGGCUCGGGCUGCACAGGAGCCCACGGGAGGCAGAGGCUCAGGCAUGGUGGGCUGCAGGUCCUGAGCCCUGCCCCGCGGGGAGGCAGCUAAGGCCCAGGGAGAAAUUGAGCGCAGCACCAGUGGGCCAGCACUGCUGGGGGACCCAGCGCACCCUCUGCAGCCGCUGGCCUGGGUGCUAAGCCCCUCAUUGCCUGGGGCUGGCAGGGCCAGCCGGCCGCUCCCAGUGCGGGGCCUGCCAAGCCCACGCCCACCCGGAACUCCAGCUGGCCCACAAGUGUGGCGUGCAGCCCCAGUUCCUGCUCCCGCCUCUCCCUCCACACCUCCCUGCAAGCUGAGGGAGCCAGCUCCAACCUUGGCCAGCCCAGAAAGGGGCUCCCACAGUGCAGCAGUGGGCUGAAGGGCCCCUCAAGUGCCGCCAAAGUGGGAGCCCAGGCAGAGGAGGCGCUGAGAGUGAGCGAGGGCUGCGAGGGCUGCCAGCAUGCUGUCACCUCUCACUUGGAGUGCUUUAUGAAACGUAGAGAGCAUAACAACAGCAAGAAUAUCGUAGCUGCUGUCUUAUGAACAUCUACUGUGUACCAGGCACUGGGUUUCUUUUUUUGAGGCAGCAUCUUGCUGUGUCACCACUAUGCAGUCUUGAUCUCCCACGCUCAAGCAGUCCUCUCACCUCAGCCUCCCAAGUAGCUAGAAGAACUACAGCUACUCAUGUGCCACUAUGCCAAGCUAAUUUUUUUUUGGUUUUUUAGUAGAGACAAGGUCUCAGCCACUGUGUUUAGUUUAACACAUGACUGUCUCAUCUAAUCCUGAUAAAUACCCUUGAAAAUAUUAACACCGCUCUUUUAUAGGUAAGGAAAGUCAGGCUCAAAAAGAUGAAGUAAGUGGCCCAGGAUGACAAACGAAGGAAAGUGGUUGAGUCAAGAUUGGAAUCUGGCCAGUGUGACUUUUAGACCCAUGUUCUCAUCUACUAAGCAAACUGUUUUCCUUCCCAUAAUCAGGAUUUGCAAGAGAAGCAUAAUUAACUUUGAAGAUGGGCGUUUGCAAUUCAUUUUCUUGGGAUGCCCAUCUGACCUUCCCUUUUCAGAUCAGCAGGCAGUUUCCUGUGCUUAGGACUCAUUCCCCUCUGCAGAAGGAACUCUGGUGAUUUUCCCACCGGGAGAGGGAGACAUGAGAUGUGGCUUCCUGUUCCAGGAAAUACCGCCCAGUCUUUUUACCCACCCUCAGCCACCCCAUGCACUAUGUUAGUCAUAGUCAGUGCAUGGCGCUAGCCAGCUCUAUGGUGAUUCUGCCGGGUAAGCCACUAGCUGUUGAGAUGACCAAAGCUCAGAAAGUGCUUGCUGCAUUUCUGUUUCUGUUGUUGACAGUGGCCUGAUAUGCAUAGCAUACUUACAUAGCUCCACUUUUCAGAGCCUCUGGCAGGUACAAAUUAAUCAAUCCCCUGGCACAGCACAGUGCUAACCACAAGGAGAAAAGAAAGAGAAGUAUGUUCCACGCAGGAGAAACUGCCAAGUUGCCAAGUGCAUCUGGUCUAGGUUUUUUUUUUUUUUUUUGGAGAGAGAGUCUCGCUCUGUCACCCAGGCUGGAGUGCAGUGGCAUGAUCUCAGCUCACUGCAACCUCCACCUACCAGGUUCAAGUGAUUCUCCUGCCUCAGCUUCCUGAGUAGCUGGGAUUACAGGUGCGCACCACCACACCCAGCUAAAUUUUGUGUUUUUAGUAGAGACAGGGUUUCACCAUGUUGGUCAGGCUAGUCUCGACCUCCUUACCUGGUGAUCUGCCCUCCUCAGCCUACCAAAGUGCUGGGAUUACAGGCAUGAGCCACCGCGCCUGGCCUAGGUUUUAAAAUGCUUCGUUCCUGAGAAGAUCUGAUAGAAGUUGAAUUUUAGUUUUAAUUCAAGAAAAGGGACACUAUAACACUUAGCCACUUUUCAGUGUGUUCAUGUCUCAACUGAGAGGUGGUGUCGGUGUUUCUACUCACUGUGUCUCUUGCGCGUGUGUGUGUAUGUAUGUAUUUUUGAGACAGAGUCUCGCUCUGUUGCCUAGGCUGGAGUGCAGUGGCACGAUCUUGGCUCACUGCAACCUCCACCUCCCCGGUUCAAGCGAUUGUCCUGCCUCAGCCACCUGAGUAGCUGGGAUUACAGGCCCGUGCCACCACGCCCAGCAAAUUUUUGUAUUUUUAGUAGAGACGGGGUUUUGCUGUGUUGGCCAGGCUGGUCUUGAACUCCUGAUUACAGGUGGGAUUACAGGCAGGAACCACCCCGCCCAGCCUCAAGUGUAUAUUGACAAGACAUUGUCCCAGGGGUAAUGACAGAAUUGAAAAUGGUGACAUGGGGCAGUGGGCUGCACGGCCACAUGUAUACAUUAAGCCUCAUAGAACUGUUCUCUCUUUCUCUCUCUCUCAUACACAUACACAUCAGUUUUAUCACAUGUGAAUUUUUAAAAUAUUUUAAGUAAGAUGGACCCUUUUCCUCAAAGAGUGUAGGUACAGUUUAAUGGGGGAUAAGACAAUGAAUUCUCUUGCUGGGCUAAAGACAGUCUAAACCACAAGAGAAGUUGAAAAAAGCAGUGCUGUGGGGCUUGAAGCCAGCAUGAGACACUGCUGGCCACGGGAAGUCUCAGCCUUGAUGGUUGGGUAGUGUGUGCUGAAGAUCAGAAAGUUUGUGGAAGGGCAGGGUAGAGGCAUGGGGGAAGGACAUACGUUUUGGGAACAGCUCACAUUCCUUUUUAAAAAAAAAAAAAAACAAAAAAACAUAGGACAUAGUUCCUAAGCUGAUGUUUGUUGAGCACCAACUCUGUACCAACUGCUAUGUUAGUUUCUGGGGACUCUGAGAUGGAAAGAAUGCAUCCCCAACUCAUCAGGGAAGAUAUACAGAUGGCAAAUAAACACAUGAAAAGAUGUUCCAAUAGCAUUAGGAGAUAUACCUAAUGCUAAAUGACUAGUUAAUGGGUGCAGCACACCAACAUGGCACAUGUAUACAUAUGUAACAAACCUGCACGUUGUGCACAUGUACCCUAAAACUUAAAGUAUAAUAAUAAUAAAAUUAAAAAAAAAAAGAUGUUCCACAUCAUAUGCCCAUUCAAAUGACUAGAUACCAUGUAAACACCUACUAGAAUGGCCAAAAUGCAAAACACUGACAACACCGAAUGGUAGUGAGAAUGUGGAGCAACAGAAACUCUCAUUCAUUGCUGGUGGGAAUGCAAAAUGGCACAGCCACUUAAAACUAAACACACUCUUACUGUGUGAUCCAGCAAUUGCACUCCUUGAGAUUUACCCGAAUUAGUUGAUAAUAGGUCCACACAAAAACCUGCACUUGAUGGUUAUAGCAGCUUUAUUCAUAAUUGCCAAAACUUAGAAGCAACCGAGAUGUCCUUCAGUAGGUGAAUGGAGAAAUAAACUGUGGUCCAUCCAGACAAUGAAAUAUUCCAUGAUAAAAAUAAAUGAGCUAUCAAGCCAUUAAAGACAUGGAGAAAGUUUAAAUGCAUAUUACUAAAUGAGGCUUGGCGCAGUGGCUCACACCUGUAAUCGCAACACUUUGGGAGGCUGAGGCAGGUGGAUCACUUGAGGUCAGGAAUUCAACAACACCCUGGCCAACAUGAUGAAACCCCGUCUGUACUAAAAAUCCACAAAUUAGCCGGGUAUGGUGGCACGUGCCUGUAGUCCCAGCUACUCGGGAGGCUGAGGCAGGAGAGUCACUUGAACCUGGGAGGUGGAGGUUUCAGUGAGCUAAGAUCGCACCACCACACUCUAGCCUGGGCGACAGAGCAAGACCCUGUCUCAAAAAACAAACAUAUUACUAAGUGAAAGAAGCCAAUCUGAAAAAGGCAGCAUACUGAGUAAUUCCACCUGUAUGACAUUCUAGAAAAGGCAAAAUUAUGGAGGCAAAAAUUAGUUGGGGAUGGUAGCGCAUGCCUGUAAUCCCAGCUACUGGGGAGGCUGAGGCAGGAGAAUCGCUUGAACCCAGGAGAUGGAGGUUGCAGUGAGUCGAGAUCGCAUCACUGCACUCCAGCCUGGGUGAAGAGCCAGACUCCACCUCAAAAAAAAAAAAGAAAAGAAAAGAAAAGAAAAAAACAAUGAUGGAGACAGUAAGAUCACUGGUUCAGGUUAAGGGAGAGAAGAGGAUGAAUAGGUAAUGCACAGAGGAUUUUUGAGGCAGUGAAUUAAAAGAAAAAAAACUCGAUCCCUGUCCUUACGGAUCUCUGGUCUAGUCGGAGUCAGCAGGCACACAGAGGCCUGCUGAGAUGGAGAAUCGAUGCUCAGAUUCUUCCUCUGUAUCCAGAAGAAGCCAGAGGAGGGUACUGCCUGGCCCUGGGAGGCUUCACUAGAGGUUUUCGAGAGGAAGAUGCACGUCUAAGGUGUGACGGGAAAGGGCCAGAAAGAGAAUGAGGGAAGAACAUUCCAAGCCACAGAAAUGGCACAUGGAAGAGAGCAGAGAUGAGAGGAGAAACCAUCUGUGACUUAGGUGGCUCAGCAGAGCUGGAGAGAGUCGGGCAAUUGAGUUGAAGCACAGGCUGGGGCCGUGCCAUGCAAGGCUUUGCCAGCUAUACAAGGGCACCACAUGCCGUGGGGAGAACCAGAGUGUUUUUAGCAGGGUGGUGUGAUCAGAUUCCUACUUCAGAAAGAUGGGCACAGUGUGAGGGAUGGAUUGGGGUGAUCAGGCUGGCUCAAGGAGUCCCAGUCAGAGAGGGCAGGCUAGAAAGAAGUAGACAAUUGAAUCGAUGUUGAAAAUAUAGAAUGUACAGGCUCUGGUGAUUGGUUGGAUGGUGAGUGGGAGAGAGGAAGGGGACCAAGGUGCUUCCCUGGGGUCUAGUUUAGAUGGGUUGAGGGCGGGGCAAUCAGAGAAAGACUAGUUGUAGAGAGAGGGAGCAGGAAAAGGGAAAUAGAGCUAGAAAGUUAAUUAGAACCAUGCUGUGAGGAUACUGAAUGCCAAGGUCAAGACUGUAUUGAAAAACCUGAGCCGAGGCUGGGCACAGUGGCUCACGCCUGUAAUCCCAGGACUUUGGGAGGCCAAGGUGGGUGGAUCACAAGGUCAAAGAGAUCGAGACCAGCUUGGCCAACAAUGGUGAAACCCUGUCUCUACUAAAAAUACAAAAAUUAGCUGGGCGUGGUGGCAUGCGCCUAUAGUCCCAGCUACUUGGGAGGCUGAGGCAGGAGAAUCUCUUGAACCCAGAAGGUAGAGGUUGCAGUGGCCUGAGAUCGUGCUACUGUACUCCAGCCUGUCAACAGAGCGAGACACCCUCUCAAAAAAAAAAAAGAAAAAAAAAACCUGAGACAAAACAAUCUUAGUGCAGAUCACUCUUUGUUACUCUGUUUCUUUGCUACAUCAGACUUUGACCAGAACCUGAGAUGGAGAUGGACAUCUGGGAGUUGCUGGAUUCUAGAAUAAACAUUUGACAGCCUUUCCCAGAGUGGCCCAUACCCAAAUUGAUAAUCAGGAUUGUGGAAGCAUAGGGAAACACUUGAUAGGAGCUGAAAAGCAGUGUACUUUUAAGAGAAUAACUUUCACUGAAUUCUAACAAUUAUUUCUGAAAGUAUUGAAUUCAACUGGUAAGAUAAACAAUCUUAAUCUCCUAUGACCCCAAGUUUCUCAGCUGGUAAAUGAAGGAAAAAGACCUGUUGAUCUCAGAAUUCUCUUGCAGCUCUGCAAUUCUAGCCUAAUAAAAAUUUUCAUCAAGAUUUAAAAAAAAAAUCUUAUAUAAGUAAAUAUAGAGUCCAGUGCUAUUUUUCAUUGAUCUUCAAACAUUUUUUUCCCCAAAUUUUAAUGCUGAAACACCAACUUGCCAAAUUUUCCAGAGUGCAAAUCCCCUGCCCAGUGAGCUGUUAUUAUUUGAAAAUAUUGUGGCCUCUAAAGCUGACUUUAUCUUUAAAAAACAAUUUUUUUUUAACCAGCAAAAGGAAUAAAUUUCCAUGUUUAUACCAAUGAGUUUCCUGAAACUAAGAAAAACUAACCAUUAUAUUGUUUCAUGUAAGGAACUUGGGUACUAUCAUAAUCCCCAUUUUAAUGAUGAGGAAAUAAAUAGGCGAAGGUAAUUAUUUCAGACUGUGUUUCCUUGACGCAGUAUUUCUGGAUGGUGAAUCUUACUCAGAUUUUGUUUUGAUGCUAUUCUUGGGAUUGACUUGAGAAGCACCAGUGGCUGACUCUUUCUUUCUCAGUGCGGAGGGGUAAAUUGGGAACAAGCUGUCUUGCUUUCAUCAUAUUAUUUGCUGUCAUCAUGAAAGGCAGGCAGUGAG